CCUCCCUCUCACCUGCUCCUCUACCUGCUCCACCCUCAAUCCACCAGAACCAUGGGCUGCUGUGGCUGCUCUGGAGGCUGUGGCUCCGGCUGUGGGGGCUGUGGCUCUGGCUGUGGGGGCUGUGGGUCCAGCUGCUGUGUGCCCAUCUGCUGCUGCAAGCCCGUGUGCUGCUGUGUGCCAGCCUGUUCCUGCACCAGCUGUGGCUCUUGUGGGGGCUCCAAGGGGUGCUGUGGCUCUUGUGGGGGCUCCAAAGGGGGCUGUGGCUCUUGUGGGGGCUCCAAGGGAGGCUGUGGCUCUUGUGGCUGCUCCCAGUGCAGUUGCUGCAAGCCCUGCUACUGUUCCUCAGGCUGUGGGUCAUCCUGCUGCCAGUCCAGCUGCUGCAAGCCCUGCUGUUCCCAGGCCAGCUGCUGUGUCCCCAUUUGCUGCCAGUGCAAAAUCUGAGGCUCUGACUUUGGACCUCAGGUGAGUCCAGCAUAUCCACACCACCCAAGAAGUGACCAGUGCUGCAUUUCAGUUCUGGCUGUCCCACAGCUCCAGGAGUUGUGUCCCCUGAAUUUUGCA